ACCAUCUUCCUCUUGCUGCCAGUGGUAGCGCUCGUCUGGCGGAGCUGGGUGAGUUGCGGCUGUGGCCGCGGCCAGGGAGACGGGCAAUCCUCCCCUCCCCCAUCCCCUUCCACACGCACAGCGCCUCCGCGGGCCUCUCCGCCCCUCCCGCGGCGGACUCUCCGCGCUUUUCUCCCGCGCAGCCGAGAGAUCGCCUCUCGGGCCUCUUGCGCAACGUCCUCGGCCUACCUGGGCCGCGCCGCUGGCGCCUGUGGACCAUUUGGACCGCGGGCUGGGGAGGGAGUCGCAGCGACGCGGUCGCCAGGCGGAGGGUCGGGACCACGGCCUCUCUCCCGACCACUGGUACCCAGCCGUCUGCUGCGAGGGCGCCCCGCCGCCGCUGAGGCGCGGGCGCGCAGGCCCGAGGCACGGCGGGCGCUGCCUGGAAGGCCCGUCUCGCAGGCCCCCGGAUCCGGCCGUUGGGGCCUCUUCCUUCUCAGGGAGCCCCAGCAUGGAGCUUUGGGCCUUGGUUUCGGGAAACUGGGACUGGCCCUGGCUGCUAGGCUGCUCCCUGCUGCUGCUUUUUGGAGAUGAGAGUUGCUCUUCCAUUUAUCCUCCAGUUACCGCGCGCUUUUGUGCCCGGGACUCAAACUGUGGACUCCUUUUGCUUAGUUUGAAAUGAGAAGCCUAGACUCUUGCCUUCCGAUAAUACAUGGCUGAAAGACACACAGAAGUCUUCAUGGAUAUAGUUGAUACAUUUAAUCAUUUAAUUCCUACUGAACACUUAGAUGAUGCCCUAUUUCUAGGAUCCAACCUGGAGAAUGAAGUCUGUGAGGAUUUUAGUGCAAGUCAAAAUGUCUUAGAGGACUCGCUGAAGAACAUGCUCAGCGAUAAGGAUCCUAUGCUAGGAUCUGCAAGUAACCAGUUCUGUUUGCCUGUUUUGGAUAGCAAUGAUCCCAAUUUCCAGAUGCCUUGUUCAACAGUUGUUGGUCUUGACGAUAUUAUGGAUGAAGGAGUUGUUAAAGAAAGUGGCAAUGAUACCAUUGAUGAAGAAGAACUGAUUUUACCUAACAGGAACUUAAGGGACAAGGUAGAAGAAAAUUCAGUGAGAUCUCCAAGAAAAUCACCUCGUUUAAUGGCACAAGAACAAGUAAGAAGUUUGCGACAGAGCACUAUUGCCAAGCGUUCAAAUGCAGCACCAUUAAGUAACACAAAAAAAGCAUCUGGGAAGACUGUAUCUACUGCUAAAGCAGGAGUGAAACAACCAGAAAGGAGUCAGGUUAAAGAAGAAGUAUGUAUGUCACUGAAACCUGAGUACCAUAAGGAGAAUAGAAGGUGCAGCCGAAAUAGCGGACAAAUUGAAGUGGUACCUGAAGUAUCAGUGUCUUCAAGUCAUUCUUCAGUGUCAUCUUGUCUUGAAAUGAAGGAUGAAGAUGGAUUAGAUUCUAAGCAUAAGUGUAAUAAUCCGGGAGAAAUAGAUGUGCCAUCUCAUGAAUUAAAUUGUUCACUUCUUUCAGAGACUUGUGUUACUAUUGGAGAAAAGAAAAAUGAAGCUUUGAUGGAAUGUAAAGCCAAGCCUGUUGGUAGUCCAUUGUUUAAGUUUUCAGAUAAAGAAGAACAUGAACAAAAUGAUUCCAUUUCAGGUAAAACGGGUGAGACUGUUGUUGAAGAAAUGAUAGCAACAAGAAAAGUUGAACAAGAUUCAAAGGAGACAGUAAAAUUAUCCCAUGAAGAUGACCAUAUUCUUGAGGACGCUGGAUCUUCUGAUAUUUCUAGUGAUGCUGCUUGUACAAAUCCAAAUAAGACAGAAAACAGCCUUGUAGGUUUGCCUAGUUGUGUAGAUGAAGUGACUGAAUGUAAUUUGGAAUUGAAGGAUACCAUGGGUAUUGCUGAUAAAACUGAGAACACCCUUGAAAGAAAUAAAAUUGAACCGUUGGGUUAUUGUGAAGAUGCGGAGUCUAAUAGGCAGUUGGAGAGCACUGAGUUUAAUAAAUCAAACUUAGAGGUGGUUGAUACUAGUACUUUUGGACCGGAAAGUAAUAUCUUGGAAAAUGCUAUUUGUGAUGUGCCUGACCAAAAUUCAAAACAGUUGAAUGCUAUAGAAAGUACUAAAAUAGAGUCCCAUGAAACAGCAAACCUUCAGGAUGACAGAAACAGCCAGUCAAGUAGCGUUUCUUACUUAGAGUCAAAAAGUGUAAAAUCCAAACAUACAAAACCUGUAAUUCAUUCUAAGCAAAACAUGACCACAGAUGCUCCGAAGAAAAUUGUUGCAGCAAAGUAUGAAGUAAUACAUAGCAAAACUAAAGUUAAUGUCAAAAGUGUGAAACGAAAUACUGAUGUACCAGAAUCUCAGCAAAAUUUUCAUAGGCCAGUCAAAGUCAGAAAAAAACAAAUUGAUAAGGAGCCAAAGAUUCAGAGUUGCAAUUCUGGGGUUAAAUCUGUGAAAAACCAAGCUCAUUCUGUACUGAAAAAAACAUUACAGGAUCAAACUUUAGUACAAAUUUUCAAGCCCUUAACUCAUUCUUUGAGUGAUAAGUCACACGCUCAUCCUGGUUGCUUGAAAGAACCUCAUCAUCCUGCACAAACUGGACAUGUAUCACAUUCUAGCCAGAAACAGUGUCAUAAGCCUCAGCAACAGGCCCCAGCAAUGAAAACCAAUAGUCACGUGAAGGAAGAGCUUGAACACCCAGGCGUUGAGCAUUUUAAGGAAGAGGAUAAACUGAAACUGAAAAAACCUGAGAAGAACCUACAACCCCGCCAAAGAAGAAGCAGCAAAAGUUUUUCUUUAGAUGAGCCACCAUUGUUCAUUCCAGAUAACAUAGCUACCAUAAGAAGAGAAGGCUCUGAUCAUAGCUCCUCAUUUGAAAGCAAAUAUAUGUGGACUCCCAGCAAGCAGUGUGGGUUUUGCAAAAAACCACAUGGCAACAGGUUUAUGGUUGGCUGUGGGAGAUGUGAUGACUGGUUUCAUGGUGAUUGUGUUGGGUUAAGUCUUUCUCAAGCACAGCAGAUGGGCGAGGAAGACAAAGAAUAUGUCUGUGUAAAAUGUUGUGCUGAAGAAGACAAAAAGACUGAAAUACUAGAUCCAGAUACUUUGGAAAACCAAGCUACAGUUGAAUUCCAUAGUGGAGAUAAAACAAUGGAGUGUGAAAAGCUUGGAUUAUCAAAACACACAACAAAUGAUAGAACCAAAUAUAUAGAUGAUACAGUGAAGCACAAGGUCAAAAUUUUAAAACGGGAGUCUGGUGAAGGCAGAAAUUCAUCAGACUGUAGAGAUAAUGAAAUUAAAAAAUGGCAGCUAGCUCCUCUUCGUAAGAUGGGACAACCAGUUUUACCUCGGAGAUCCUCAGAAGAAAAAAGUGAAAAAAUACCGAAAGAGUCUACAACUGUUACUUGCACAGGAGAAAAAGCUUCAAAACCAGGUACUCAUGAGAAGCAAGAGAUGAAAAAGAAGAAAGUUGAAAAAGGAGUGCUUAAUGUACAUCCUGCUGCUUCUGCUUCCAAGCCUUCUGCAGAUCAGAUCAGGCAAAGUGUCAGACAUUCUCUCAAAGACAUUCUUAUGAAGAGACUUACAGACUCAAAUUUGAAGGUACCAGAGGAAAAGGCAGCAAAAGUUGCCACAAAAAUUGAGAAAGAGCUUUUCUCUUUUUUUCGGGACACAGAUGCUAAAUAUAAGAACAAAUAUAGAAGUUUGAUGUUUAAUUUGAAAGAUCCUAAAAACAAUAUAUUAUUUAAAAAAGUACUGAAAGGAGAAGUAACUCCUGAUCAUCUUAUCAGAAUGAGUCCAGAAGAACUAGCUUCUAAAGAGUUAGCUGCUUGGAGACGAAGAGAAAACAGACAUACCAUAGAAAUGAUUGAGAAAGAGCAGAGAGAAGUGGAACGACGGCCAAUCACCAAAAUAACUCAUAAAGGUGAAAUAGAAAUUGAGAGUGAUGCCCCAAUGAAAGAACAGGAAGCAGCCAUGGAGAUUCAGGAACCAGCCGCCAAUAAGUCAUUGGAGAAGCCAGAAGGAUCUGAAAAACAAAAAGAGGAGGUUGACUCUAUGUCUAAAGAUACCACUAGUCAACACAGACAGCAUCUUUUUGAUCUCAACUGCAAAAUCUGCAUAGGUCGAAUGGCACCACCUGUAGAUGAUCUUUCUCCAAAAAAAGUAAAAGUUGUUGUAGGAGUAGCUCGCAAACAUUCAGACAAUGAAGCAGAAAGUAUAGCAGAUGCAUUAUCUUCAACCUCAAAUAUUUUGGCUUCUGAAUUCUUUGAGGAGGAGAAACAGGAGUCUCCAAAGUCAACGUUCUCUCCUGCUCCACGUCCAGAGAUGCCUGGAACUGUUGAAGUUGAGUCUACCUUUCUGGCUCGAUUGAACUUCAUCUGGAAAGGUUUUAUCAACAUGCCUUCUGUGGCAAAAUUUGUUACCAAAGCCUAUCCAGUAUCUGGCUCCCCAGAAUACCUGACAGAGGACCUACCAGAUAGUAUUCAAGUAGGUGGCAGGAUAUCACCUCAGACAGUUUGGGAUUAUGUGGAAAAAAUAAAAGCAUCAGGAACCAAGGAAAUUUGUGUGGUUCGCUUCACACCAGUAACUGAAGAAGAUCAAAUUUCUUAUACUUUGCUCUUUGCAUACUUCAGUAGCAGAAAGCGCUAUGGAGUAGCUGCUAACAACAUGAAGCAGGUUAAAGAUAUGUACCUUAUUCCUUUGGGUGCCACAGAUAAAAUUCCACACCCUCUUGUGCCUUUUGAUGGACCUGGGCUUGAACUGCAUAGACCUAAUCUAUUGUUGGGCUUAAUUAUUCGUCAGAAACUGAAGCGACAGCACAGUGCCUGUGCUAGUACUAGUCAUAUAGCUGAGACUCCUGAAAGUGCACCACCAAUAGCAUUGCCACCUGAUAAAAAAAGUAAAAUAGAAGUUUCUACAGAAGAAGCACCAGAGGAAGAAAAUGACUUUUUUAAUUCUUUUACAACUGUAUUACACAAGCAGAGAAAUAAACCUCAGCAGAAUCUUCAGGAAGACCUUCCAACAGCAGUUGAACCUUUAAUGGAAGUCACCAAACAGGAGCCACCAAAACCUUUAAGAUUUCUUCCUGGCGUGUUGAUUGGCUGGGAGAAUCAACCUACUACUCUGGAAUUAGCAAAUAAACCUCUUCCUGUGGAUGAUAUACUUCAAAGCCUUUUGGGCACCACUGGUCAAGUAUAUGACCAGGCCCAGUCAGUGAUGGAACAAAACACUGUUAAAGAAAUUCCAUUUUUAAAUGAGCAGACCAACUCAAAAAUAGAGAAAACAGAUAAUGUGGAAGUAACUGAUGGUGAAAACAAGGAGAUAAAAGUUAAAGUAGAUAAUAUUUCAGAAUCUACAGAUAAGUCAGCAGAAAUAGAAACAUCAGUAGUAGGGUCCUCUUCCAUUUCUGCAGGGUCUUUGACGAGUCUUAGUCUCAGAGGUAAGCCACCAGAUGUUUCUACAGAAGCAUUUUUAACAAAUUUAUCAAUUCAGUCAAAACAAGAGGAAACUGUGGAGAGUAAAGAGAAAACAUUAAAAAGACAGCUUCAGGAAGAUCAAGAGAAUAAUUUGCAAGAUAACCAGACUUCAAAUAGUUCUCCAUGCAGAUCUAAUGUAGGAAAAGGAAACAUAGAUGGUAAUGUGAGCUGUAGUGAAAACCUUGUUGCUAAUACAGCGAGGUCUCCACAGUUUAUCAACCUGAAAAGGGAUCCUAGGCAAGCAGCAGGACGAAGUCAGCCUGUAACUACUUCAGAAAGCAAAGAUGGAGAUAGUUGCCGGAAUGGAGAAAAACACAUGCUGCCUGGCCUGUCACACAACAAGGAGCACUUAACAGAACAAAUCAAUGUAGAGGAAAAGUUGUGUUCUGCAGAGAAAAACUCGUGUGUUCAGCAGAGUGACAAUUUAAAAGUUGCACAAAACUCACCAUCAGUAGAAAACAUACAGACUUCUCAAGCAGAACAAGCAAAACCCUUACAGGAGGAUAUUUUAAUGCAAAAUAUUGAAACUGUGCACCCAUUUCGAAGAGGAUCAGCAGUAGCGACAUCUCAUUUUGAAGUUGGAAACACAUGUCCAUCAGAAUUUCCUUCUAAAAGCAUCACCUUUACUUCCAGAAGCACCAGCCCCAGAACAAGUACAAACUUUUCACCCAUGAGGCCACAGCAGCCCAACCUUCAGCAUCUCAAGUCUAGCCCACCUGGAUUUCCAUUUCCAGGGCCUCCUAAUUUUCCCCCACAAAGCAUGUUUGGAUUUCCACCACAUUUGCCACCUCCAUUACUUCCCCCUCCAGGCUUUGGCUUUGCUCAAAAUCCCAUGGUUCCCUGGCCACCUGUUGUUCAUCUCCCAGGUCAGCCACAGCGUAUGAUGGGUCCUCUCUCACAAGCAUCAAGGUAUAUAGGCCCGCAGAAUUUUUACCAGGUUAAAGACAUUCGGAGGCCAGAAAGGCGCCAUAGUGACCCUUGGGGUAGGCAAGACCAACAGCAACUGGAUAGGCCAUUUAAUAGGGGUAAAGGGGACCGCCAGAGAUUUUAUAGUGAUUCACACCAUUUGAAAAGAGAGCGACAUGAAAAGGAAUGGGAGCAAGAAUCUGAAAGGCAUAGACGCAGAGACAGAAGCCAAGACAAGGACAGAGACAGAAAAAGCAGGGAGGAAGGGCACAAAGAUAAAGAGAGGGCACGGUUAUCACAUGGUGAUCGAGGAACAGAUGGAAAAGCAAGCAGAGAUAGUAGGAAUGUAGACAAGAAGCCAGAUAAACCUAAAAGUGAAGACUAUGAGAAGGACAAAGAACGAGAGAAAAGUAAACACAGAGAAGGAGAAAAGGACAGGGAUAGGUACCACAAAGAUAGGGACCACACUGACAGAACUAAAAGCAAAAGGUAAAAUUUGCAGGCUGCUUCAGGAUUACAUUUAAAUAACUGUUAAAAUGUUGUAUCUUGUAAACAAAAGAAAGAUUGCCUGCUAGGAUUGUGCCAUCUUUAAAAUUUUUACUAUUGGUCAUUUGCAGAACAGUAAAUUCUGUGUGUUGGUACAGAGUGCUCUGUACCAGUGCUCAUCAUCCCUUCUUCAUACCAACGGUCCCUAGUUAUAGGAAUUUAAUAUUUUUAAAAGUUUUACAUUGCUGUAUAUUCAAAGAUUUGUUUUAUUAAUAUGCAAUAAAGGCUUAGAAAUUUUAGUUUUAUUCCUUAAUUGGUAAAUAUGGUUAACUAUGGAAUAUAUUUACUUCCUCUAGUGAAUGUCCUUUAUAUAAUGACUAAUUUGGGAGUAAUGUGUGCUCUGUAAGUUUGUUUUAAAUUGCACUGUUUUUAAAGAAACUGUAGAGGAGCAACAAAAAUCCAAGCAACUUCAUAAUCAGAUUAUGCUAAUCAUUUAGUUGAGCAGUUUUUGACCAAGAAUCAGAAGCCCAAGGGGUACAUUUAUUGCUUUAAUCUGCACUCAUUGAAGUCAUUUAUUACCAUAUACUACAGCUUUGUGGUAGGCCAUUAUUUUCAUUUUCAUUUUUGGCUCUUCAGAAACUUGAAUACUUAAGCUUGUACAUGAUCUUGUGUUUUGCUAUCCUUUUUACUGUAAAAUGUAAAUAUUUUAAGGGAUAUUUUGAUUCUAAAUAUGAUAAAAUAAUUUCUCACCUAUUUUGUGUGUGUGACUUGAAAUUCAGUAGUAAAAGAAUUUCUUCUUUAAAGCUUUAAUUACCUUCAGACAUUGAUUUUUUGUUACUCAGCCAAGAACAUAUAGAAAUAGCUAUCUAUGUCAGGCAUUAGAUGAGGGGAAAAACAAUUUUUUUAAAAUCUUAAAUUGUAGGCUGAGAUGAAUUGUGUAGUUCUAAAGAGGCUAGAAUUUAGAACUACCUGUGAAACACUGUGCAGCUAUAGCCCACUUUAUAGGUAAGUUUCUGAAAACUUUUACACCAUCGCAAUUUGGUACUCUGACUCACUAAUCAUUAAAAUUAAAGACCGCAGAACUUGAAGAGAAAUAUGUUUUGAAUCCUUUUAUAAAAUGUGCGAUUUAGCCUAAUUCGUAAAGUAACUGUACAGUUUCAUAUGCCAGUUUUACUUGAAAAAAAAAUAUGAAAACUAUUGUUAAUUCAAAUCUAAAUUUAUUUAAACCCUAAAACACAUGGUUUUGAUGGCUGUAAUUUAAAGUAAGAGCUAUCAAAUGAUGCUGACAAAAGAAAAACCUUCCAAAAUACAAAAGAAAGAGAACUCUAUUAUUUACUUACCUGUAUUAAUGAAGAAAAAUAUAAAUAAUUCCACAAAAUUGAUUGUUUUCCUAAAGAGCUUAAAGAUUAGAGUUAAAAAUUGGUUUUGAAACAGAAUUAUCCUUGUUAUUUUUGCUGGAGAGAAGGGAGGAAAUUCAGAACCAAACAUUCUAUUUAAUUUGCAAUGACUUGCAGUACUUUUUUCCCUAUCCUUAUCCUGUGAAACUUACUAUCAUAAGGUUCUAAAACAGAGAACUUGUGUUUAAAUAAAGCCCGUUUAACUUUGGUCCACUUUUCUUUUGGAAAUUAACUUGUUAGAAAACAAAGUUAGUUCCCAAACAAAACAAAAUCUAAGUUAUAAUUUGCACCAUUACAAAGAAAUUGCUGUCAGGGUUUUACACAUUUUAAAAACAUUUCAAUUUCAAAUGUGUAUAUCGUCAAUAAAUCUACCUUUACUGAUAUAUCUGGUUGAGGGAAUAUCAGACUCCAGAUUUCUUUUGCAAGAUGAAAGUAAAAACGAGUGGGUUAAUGAAUGAAAACAAGCUUUUAGGUCAGUUUUUGAUCACCUCUUCGCUAAUAGUUUUUUCUACAUAUCUAAAAUUCUUUAAUCAGUUCUGAUCGAAUCUUGAUACAUGUUUUUAAAAUAGGCAAGGCCCAUAUAGCUUUCUAUUAGGGAUGAGCAUCUCCAGGGGUUAGAGGCAGAUCUUGUAACCGCUGAUUGACUGAAACAUUUUAUGGAGAAUAGGGAAGGUAUGGUCAUAUUAGCUAUUUGAGGUUUUCCUUUUGAGGAAAAAAAGGGAAAAUGAGCAGAUUUUUCAAUGAGUAGUAGAUCCAAAGCCAUUCUCAGUCCCAGGUACAACCAGCCUUACACAAACUAGUGAAUUACAUGAAUUUCAUCUUUCAGUUUCUCCUGUUUUAAGAAAAAACCUGCUCUUUAAAAAAAGUUUUACACUUAAAAAAACUUAGAAUCAUCUUAAGACAGUGAAUGCAUACCUCUAUUAGGUAAAAGUACCAGGGCAUCUCAGUACCUGUAAAGUUCACCCCAUGUAAUCUUUGUGGCAAUCAGAAAGCCUCCUUGAGCCCUCUGUAAGGCAUCCCUGGUUUUGAGCACUUAGUAUAAACAUUGGUCAACUCAAAGGUGAAGGCUUAGAGCUGAGGAAACUGGAACUUAGAGAAGUUGGGAAACUUGGCCAGGUUACCCUGCUGUUGUCAGAGCAGGAAUCCUACCUAGCUCAGUUCUUUUCUCUAAAGUCCAUGUGCUUAGCAAUUGUGCUCUGAGAAUUGAGAAUGAGAAAAAGAAGCAAAAGCCUGAUGAUCAUAUAUACCUUUCAUAGCCCUCUUUCUUUGCGUUCCACUGAACUGUCUGAAACCCUUCACUGAGCAACCCAACUGUUCAGUGUGAGUCAGAAGACACAACCAAAAACCUGUAAGUUCUUUUGUACGGAUUUGCAAAAUUUAUAUUAAUCACAAAUCCUAAUUCUCUAUUCCUGUUUUCUAUUGCUGUUGUGAUGAAUUACUACAAGUGUAGUGGCUUAAAACCACACAAAUUUAUGAUCUUACGGUUCUGUGGAUCAGAAGUCUGUGCAGAUCUCACUGGGUAAGAUCAAGGUGUCAGCAAGAUGCAUUCAUUUUCUGGAGACUUUCAGGGAGAUUCCUUUUUUUUUGCGCCUUGGUUUCUAGCUUCUAGAGGGCACCCAAUUUCCUUGGCUCAUGAUCCCUUCCUCCAUAUUUGAAGCCAGCAGUGUGGGACCCAGUCUUUCUCUAGUAUCUCUGACCUUCCCUUCUGAUUCCCUCUUCUACUACAAAGGACCCUUGUGAUUACAUUGACCCCACCCAGAUAAUCCAGGGUAAUGUUCCUAUUUUCAGGUCAGCUGAUGAGCAACUUAAAUUCCAUCUGUGACCUUAAUUCCCUAUUCCCAUGUAACCUAACAUAUUUACAGGUGUUCCAAGGAUUGGGGUGUAGACAUCUUUUGGGGGAUUAUCAUCUACCAACAGCCCUUGACUUACUAAUUGUAGUUUAUUGUGGGUGAAUUAAUCUGAAAUCUUUAUAGAAUAGCUAAGGCUAUAGUAAAUACAUGUGAAAAAUUUAAGAACAAUAACACCAGCAAUAGAGAAGAAAAUGGAGUGAAAAGUGAAGCCACUCCAUGUUAACGUGUGUGUUAACAUAAAACUACCCGUCAACAGGUAACUUUACUCUGUUGUUCCUAAGUUUUUAAUAGUAGCUGUGUUUUUAAAGUUUAUGAACCAAACUUAAAUGCAUUAUGAGAGCUUGAUAAUGAACCAGAUCUUAGUAAAACAGUAUUUUAACAUUUGGAUAUACUAGUUGUACUAUGCUUAUCUCAGAUCCCUGUAACACUGGUCAGGCUACAACUUACUAAUGACUACAAAGAACUAUAUACACAAUCAGGUUUAUUUCUGUCUCUUAAAGCAAAUUGCAAAUAAAAUUGGUUACUGCUUUUAAAAAGGUGCCAAACACCCUAAUUCUUUGAUUUCUGUUUCACAAUUAUAGUAAUAUGUAGAGCAAAAAAGUAGUGAGUUGAAAACAGAUCAGUAGCAAGAAGUCCUUUGAAAACUUGAGUUCACCAUGUCAAGUUUCAUCUUAUAGAUAGAUGCAGAGCAGAGUCAUUGAGGGAAAUAGCCUAAGCACUCAAAGGGCAGUGAAUCCAAUAUAACUCUAAAUAUCCCCAAAAUACUUUUUCUAUGAAAUAAUUCAGUGUGUGCAUGUCCAUGUGUGUAUAUAUACAUAUAUGUUAGCCCAAGCUGUCUUUUAAAACUCCUUAUUUUAAGAUAAUUUUGUCCUCAAAGUAAUGAUUUUUUUCAGGAACUUAUUAUUUAUAAGGAGACCAAAAAGGUAAAUAUUACUGCACCUUAUUUUUAAAAAAUGUUCCGUUUACAUUCAACACUUUGAGAAACCUCAUACAUUUAUAGUAAAAUCUUAAAGGUCUUUCUGUAGCCAAUCAUUUUUAUUUCGUACUGGAAAAGCAUUUCACAUAGGAAAUCGUCAACACCAUUAUCACCAGGAUAGCAAAAAUAGGAAGCGGGAAUAGUGUUGAUUUGUUACAUGAACUUUCCAGGAUUUUAAGGUGAAAAAUAUAUUUUCAAGUCAUUUUGAUUUAUAGGAGAAAAGGCAGCAGUUUUCAGUUCUUAAAUAUUGUCUGCCUAUUCUGCAAGCACAAUUUUCUGCGUUUGGAAUUCAAUGAUGAGCAAAAUGGGAAAGUUCCAAUUUUGUGGAGAUUACAGGUAGAAAAGUUAUAAAAUCUGAACGUAAAAUUGCAACUGUGAAAAGCUUUAAGGCAGCAAUUCUCAAACUUUUGUUUUCAAGACCCCUUACACUCUUAAAAAUUGAGAAUGUCAAAGCUUUUGUUUAUAUGGCUUAUAUCAUUAUUUAGCAUACUAGAAAAUCAAAUGAUAAACGUUAAAAAUAUUUGUUAAUGAUAAUCUCAUCUGUUAAUGUAACAUUUAUAUAAAAGUUAACUUCCAAACUAAUUUAGUAAGAAGAGUGUCAUUGUCUUGAUUUUUGCAUAUUUCCAAUUUCUGACUUAGGGCUGGAUUCUCUUACCUGCCCUGCAUUCAGUGUUUUGUAGUAUGUCAUUUUAUUUGAAAUAUAUGAAGAAAAUCUGGCUAUAUGUGCAUUUGUUUUUGGGAAAGGGAGGACUCUGGAUUCCUUGAAAAGAUCGCAGGGGUUCUUGGACCAUAGUUUGGGAAGUGCUAUUUUAAAGAAAAGGCACACUUUAUUAUGAGAGAACACAUGGCCGAAUAUGAUGGGAGUGUGGUUCAGGCAGUUUCUUCUUUUGUAAGCUUUCAUAAAACAGCCUUCUUUUUAUACAUAAAGUAUGUUUUCUGAAAGGUUAGAUUUGAUUACCAGCUGCCAAAAGGAAUUUCUUCAGAGCAUUUAUCCUUAUGAUCUGAGUAUCUCCAAAGUUAAAUGCAAUAGUAUGGAGCAAUACCAGUUUAGGUCACAGUUUUUCAGCAAAAUUUGAUGGAGUUGUUUUAAGUGGUUUCCGUUAAAAAAACAAACCUUUGAAUCAAUGUGUAAACAUUCUGCAAUUCUACCUUAUAUUCUACCCUCACACUUCCUAGUAUUAAUAUGAACUGUAUGUUUGGAAACAUUUGUGCCCUGUCAAAUGGUGUUGACAUUCUUAACUCUGGUCGUAGGUCCUUUUAGGAAUGUCUGUAGCCUUUUGAUUGGAAUGGAGUGGCUAAAAUAAGACAAAAAUCUCUAAUAGUUUUUGAAUGAUAAAUUACUACCUCGUUACUUUGUAUAGACUGGAAUCUGCACAGAAAUGUGUAUUCAUCAGCCCUUAUUUUUUGUAAAUCUUUUCUCUAAUUACUUGAUGAUUAAUUUCAUAUUUUUCCUUUUGAACAUUACAUGCUGCUUAUUACUAAGAUUUUUUUCUCCAGAUGACCUAUUCUACCUGUUAGUUCACCAAGUCAGUCAUAUGUUGCCGGUUGCCAAGUGGCAAAAUUAUCACAGAUAUCAAACUCAGAAAAUGUCAGGUAACAACAGCAGUAACUGCUUUCCAACCUGCAGUGGUGGACUGGGAGUGGGAAGUGAAAGUUCUGUUCACAAUUGUAUCAGUAACUGUUUUGGGAAAAAUAAUAUUUUUUCAAGUUAUGCUAUCAACAGUACUAAAUUGUUAGGAUAGUAAUUUUCCAUGGCAUUGUUUAGAACCUAUUUUAUGCCCAAUUUUGAGAUCUGUAUAGACUUGAAAGCAGUUAAACACAAAUUAAGGUUAAUUUUUUAAUUUGAUCAGUUAAUAUGAGUACAUGGUUUUAAAAAGUCAAAUAGUUCUACAAGGUUCAUAAGCAAAAAGCAACAGGCUUCUGCACUACUCUUCUCUCCAGAGGCAACCAUUUUUAAUUCUUUUAGAUAUUUAGGAUAUUUGCCUUCAUGUUUGUGAUAUGCAUAUGCUAUGUUUUAAGUUGCACAUAUUGUAAUAUCUAUUGAUGUCUUACUAUAAAAGAUAAGGAUUUAGCUCUUACCAGCCUGUUCUCCUCUCCUCUCACCUUCUCUUUCUACAUUCAUGCAAUAAUUUUUGGUUUAAAUCUAUGUUCAAGUUUUACAUUGUUGAAUCAUAUAAAUAAGUUGUAGCUAAGCCAUGUAAUACAAUAUGGUUACAUUGCUUUGUAUAAUUUUUAUUUUUCCUUUGAUUAAUAACUUGAUUUUUUUCUUAUUUGUACCUAUCCCUAAUUCAUUCCCAACUGAAUUUUAAACAUUUUAAAGUUCAGCUUACACAUUGAUUUUUAAAAUUGUGUUUACACGUUGAUUUUAAAAUGUAAGCAUUAGGGAUAGGUAAAAAGUGAAUAAGCAAAGUGAAUAAGCACAUUCUGUGAAUAAGCACUGAACUAAUGGAGUUAAAACAUGAAUCAAAAUAUAUACAGAUAAAUUAGAUGUAGGAAAAACAAUCAGAACCUUCAGUGACAUUUUACAAUCUUAUCAAAAAGAUAUGUUAGCAUUUAGACUAUUUCAGGUAAUAUAGUAAACAGUUGAUUCCCCGUAAGCAAUGUAUCAAAGAAAUAACUAUCAAAAUAACUGCAUUUAUGUAUAGUGUGUACUAAAAUCUCUAGUGUUAACUUAUGUAACCUCAUUUUGUUCAUCUCCAUCAUAAACAUUGUAUCCUUCUAAUUUAAUUAGUUCAAUGUUUUUUGGUUCCUGAAAAAAUACAACAUCUUUAAUUUUGCCAACAAAAUUGGUUUUAAAAAUCUCUUGAGUAACGAUAUUUACCUUUCUACCAUAUUCAAAGCCCCCUAGAUAACAAAUGCCAUCAUAGUUUAGAGCCACAAAGUUUUUAUGUGGAUCAAUAUCCUCGGAAAGAAUUAGACUGUUAUUUAUGUAGGCCUUGAUAAGAGUCUGAUUUUGAAUUACAACUACAUGGUGCCAUUUAUUACAACAGAAUGUGCCAUUGUUAUAGCUCAUAGGCACAGAGAUUCUUUCUCCCAAGUUAACUGCUAUUUUCAAGGUCUGAUUAUGGAGACCAAUUGCCAGAAAAUCAUUUUCUUCAUUUUGAGCUAUUCCCAUCCAUACAAUUAGACCUUCUGUUUUAGUGGUACUGAAAUUUAAGGAUAUAGUAGUGAACUGGAGGUUUCUCAUUCUAUAAUUUGGAUCAAUGUAUUUAAUGUAAGAAUUACCCAUAAAUUUUGCAGUUGAAAAUGAAGUUUUGUUUUCACAAUACCUUCCCACCCAACCCAAAGUACACAGGCAACUGUAAGAAAAUGAUUGGUCAGGUAUACAUAAAGAUUGGUGGAGGCAAAGAUUAUUCAAACAGGACACAGACUGGUUACAUGUAUUUCCAGCCCAAUCUGGCAAACAUCUGCAAGAAAAAGUUGUGCCAUUUACUGUACAUUCACCUCCAUUUCUGCAUGUGUUGUACCCACAGGCUGUCCCAUCACAGUCACCUACAUUUGAGCCACCUUUUGCUCCAAAUUCAGUUAAUUGUAAUUCUUGAUUAUUUAUGAUAACUUGUCGGAUACAGCCUUGAAAACCUACAGGUUCAUUUUCUAUUGCCAUGGGAUUUACAAGAUUUAAAGAAGAUACUCCUCCAAUAUAGAAGUCUGUAUUUGUGUCCAGAGAACUCAUUUUAGUGGAGGCCUUUUCUGUUACAUUUAUCCCAUCUAGAUCCAGGUAGCCUUCUGCACCAACUCUUCCUGCUUUUAUUAUAUGCCAAGUACUUCCGUUUAUAGUUACUUUUUGGAGAGUUUCUAGAAUGAUAGUUCUGUCGCCAAGGUUGUAGCGAAGUUGAACGGAACUAUUUACUAAAGAGAUGCAUAAAAAAUCACCUGCAAGAAAGCAAACAGUAAGUUUGAUUAGCAACAGUAAAAGUUUCCAUUGAAAACUUUUGCUGUUUCUGGCCAAGUUGGAUAAGUUUUAGUUAUGGGGAAAAAAGUAACAGAUCUUGAGCACAAUUGUGUUAGUUUUGUUUCCACUCACAGAGCAAAAUGCAUAUAUCCUGUAUUCUUUCAUUUUGUUCAGCAAUUGGCUACAUAAAUUUUCUCUAGUUGUGGACAGUUCUCAUUGAAUGAAUAUAUUGUGGUAGUAAGUUAAAGUGAGGUUUUUCUUCAAAUGAAAGCCUGUUCCUUAUGAUACCAUUUAAUGGCAUUCACUAUUGUCAGGCUAGGUACCUAUAAAUUCUCUGCACAUUCCUGGCUCCUUUCCUGUCUCUCCAACCUUACCUGGAAUGUUCUCUUUCCCCAUCCUUACACUCUCUUUACUUCAACAACACUGACUUUGUUAAUUAAGGAUUUCAUUCGCCUGUUUUCUAGGAACACUCCGCCACCCCAUUCCACCUCAACUAGAUAACUCCUACCUGUCCUUCAGGUUUCAGAUCAAGUGUCACUUCCUCAGAGAAGUUUUCCUUGAUUUCCCAGAGCUGGUCAGGAAUUUUUUUCUGUCAGUGCCUUAAUAUCACUAGGUUUCCCUCCAUUACAGUAUAUCUCAUUUUAUAAUUAUAUAGUCGUGUGAAGAAAUAGGAACAAAUACCAUCCAGCAUCUGAAGUUGCAAUGAGGCAUUCAGAAGAAAAGUAAAGGCAAUUCUGCAAGCUUGGAAAAAGCAUGUUCUUCACUGUAAGAUUGCUUGAAGAGGAUAGCAAAAUGACUUAUUAAUAAUGAACCACGCAGAAGUCUCCACGAAACAUUUUCUUCUCCCUCUGAAAUUUCCCAACCUUUUUCUUUUCUCAUCCAGGGAUAUUCGGCAUUAUGCUACACUACUUCUUCCUCCCUCCAGAGUGCCUAUUUCCACACCUCCCUCCUGCAAAUGGUGUUCUUUCCUUCUAUUCUCCAUUGUGGUCUAUACCAAGCCAUUCUAGACUGGUUGGAAUGUUUGGCAGCUCUAUAGUUCUUCACCUAUCAAACUACGUUCUCUAGCUUUAUUUUCCUCAUAGGGAAUUUUUAGUGAGUAUACUAUGUCGUUACAUAUGUGAUAUUUGGUUAACAGCUGCUUUAUCCACUAGGUUGUAAGCUUUAUGAGAACAGGGUCUGUGUUUGGUUUGGUCCAACAGUUGAUUCCCAGCACCCAAAACGGUAUCUGGCCCAUAAAUAGAUGCUAAAUAAUUAUUAAAUAAAGAAAUACGUUUGUAGGGUUGUGGGUUGAGAUGACUCAGAAUAUUUCUCAAAUAAUAGUUUUAGCUUGAAAGCAAAAACUUUUUUCCUAUAAUGACAUGAAAAUUGUUUUAAAAAUUCAUAACAAAGAAACUCAGUUUAUUUGCAUAAUUUCUAACAUGUAUAGCAUUUUUAACUAUAAGGAAAGAGAAGCAACAUUAUAAACUUUCAGAUUAGGAAAGAAAAAAUAUACAUUGGGUUAUACCACCAAAAACUGGAACAAGUAAACAUAAUUGAUAAUUAAGUUCAAAAAAUUUAUAGCAACCUAAAUAUACUUUGUGGCCUGCAAGUGAACACAAACCAGUUAUCUUUUGCAAGAUUAUGGAGGAAGCUUUUCUUGCUCCUUGUGUUGUAGAGUGUUCCUGUAGUAAACAAUUUUAUAGUGAAGAGCUACAUUAGAAUAAAAAAUAUCUAAGAAAUGAUUAGGAAAGCUGAAGCUGUGAUCUAUACUAUCACUGGUCAUGUUGCCAACCAGAAGAAAGAGCAAGGAUAGCUUCUGCGAAGAAAGGAUUAUUUUAACUCAGCUAGUAUGUUCUUACGAAAAAUUGACAAAAAGUUUUCUUUCUGUGGCUAUGGAAGCUAAAAGCUGUAUUAGCUUAAAAAAUCAUAGACUUUUAAAUUUCAUUGCGUUAGGAUAUGAUGCUCUAGUUAUGGGUCAUAAGUACACAUUGGCAUUAUUAUUAUUAUUAUUAUUAUUAUUAUUAUUAUUAUUAUUAUUAUUUUGAGACCAGAGUCCUGCUCUGUCCCCCAAGCUGGAGUGCAAUGGUGCAAUCUCGGCUCACUGCAACCUCCAUCUCCCGGGCUGCCUCAGUUUCCCGAGUAUCUGGGACUACAGGCACUGGCCAUCACGGCCGGCUAAUUUUUGUAUUUUGGGUAGAGCGAGGUUUUACCAUGUUGGCCAGGCUGGUCUUGACCUCCUGACUUCAGGUGAUCCGCCCACCUCGGCCUCCCAAAGUGGUGGGAUUACAGGCAUAUGCCACUGCACCUGGCCUUGGAUUCGCAUUAGAGUAAGAAAAUGUAAUGAACAGUCCUUACAAGAAACAGAGCUCAAAUAGGAUAAAGAUCAUAAAUGAAUUCACUUUGGCUAUUUAAUGCCCACUCAACCAUGGCUGAGGCUUCUCCCACCUUUGUUCUGCUAUUGUUUCUACCUCAUCAUCUGCUAUCCCACCGUGCUUUAUUAUAGAUAAGAGAAACCUUGUAGGACCUAAUAUUUGUGAAGAGACUACAGAAUCAGCAUAUCAGGGGAAUUGUAUAUACAUUUUUUUCUGUAGAAAAGGAAAGCAAUGGUAAUUUAAACUUAUUUAUAUAUUUUUAAUAUAGUUUAAUUAUUUGAGUAUGUUUUAACUUCACAUUGCAAUGACUAGGCCUUUUUAUACACGUUGGGAGGAUUAUAACUAUAUCAGAUGAAUUCAGGCUUUGAUUAAUUUGUGCUUAACAAAAUGUUGAUAAUUUUUAUAUAUCAAAAAUCUUUUAAAGGUGUUAAAUUUUUAGCAGAAAUAGAUGAAAAGGGACCAGAGUCUUAUUUCUUUAAAAUAUCUUUCAAAAAUCAGAGAUCUGAGAUCAUCUAGUAUAAUUUUCAAGUUAUCAUUUUGUUUUAAAUUUUACACUACUUGAGAGUACUCAAAUUAUUAACCUCUAAAGAGAUACAGAAACCAUGUUAAUUUAGAAUUUGGUUUUCAAUAUGUGAAAACCACAUUGGCUGCUUUUAUUAAAAUUUUUGGAUUUUAACUUUGUGUAUUGUUUGGUUAGUUUUUACUAAUAGGUCCUCUUAGCAGAGGAUCAACUAUGAAGACUUGGUUAAUGUUUACAUCAGGCACAGUUCUUAGAGAAGGUACAAAGUACAGGACUGUCAGCUGCAUUUUCUGCAACCUUAAAUAAAUGAGAGACUUCAAAUAAACUUGUUAUAUCACUUGAUUACUAAAAAAUAAGUUUAUGCCUUUCAUCUGAUAAUUGUUUUUGGUUAAUCUAGGUUUAAGCAUGUAGAACUUAUAUUUUUAAUAUUUAAAAAUUUUCAUGAUUUUCUUAUAUAAGUGUCAAAUGCAGCAUCAAUCGUGUGAAACUAAUGAAUCUCUGUAAGUAGUGUCUGAUGGCAUAAAAAAGGAAACUCUUGAUUGUCUUGAACUACAUGCAUUGAAUAACAGAUGUAAGAAGAUGUGCUCUUGCCCUCCUAUGUGUAUUAGUGUGUAUGAGCUUUAUAUUUCAUAUACACAAACAAAUAUGUAUCGUUGUACUGAUUAUAAAACUGUAGUACAAUAUUCCCAGCCAGUCACAAUCCUGAAUAUACCUUGAUUUUCUGCCCUCUUACAUAGGUCCCACUUAACAUUAAUUUUGAGUUUUAUUAGCAAUAUAACUGAAGCUGAUUGUCUUUUAAUGUCUCUUGAUUUAUAAAUAGAAAAUUUAUGUUUGUAUGUGGUUCUCCUAUUUGACAUUUUCACAGGGAGAUUUAAUCAUGAAUUUAAAACCAAAUAUCUCAGGAGAACAAAUUUCUUCUGAGCUGUAUUUUAUAGCUCAAUUGUACUUUUUCUCUUUGAAAUUAUUUUGAGGGUAUUUCAGAAGUGCAUUGAGGUGGAACCACUUUGGUCGAAUUCCCUGAUAUUCUUAUCAUUUAGAAGCAAGUCAAGACACUUCUAUAAGAACUACUUAGAUUAUGAUCAUUAGAGCACCAUUUUUGCUAAUGAUGUGAAAUUUAGCAAAUGUAAUUAUUUCUCAAUAUCAAAAUUGUUUCUCAUUUUCUGAGAGACAAGAUCAAAGAAAGUCAAAUGUAAGAUUUUAAAAAUACUUAGCAAUAGAGAUGUAACUAUAUGUGCAGAUGUCUUUGUCAGAAUUUUGGAGAAAUGAAUGAAAAUGGAUAUCAAGGGUAAAGUAAAACCUAAAAAAUUAAAUUUUAAAACACUAA